GCCCGCCCUGGCCGAGCGUAGCUGGCGGACCAGAGCCGGUAGCGAGGUUGGGAGAGACGGAGCGGACCUCAGCGCUGAAGCAGAAGCCCCCGGAGCUGCGGUCUCCCCGCCGCGGCUGAGCCAUGCGGCUCCCUGACCUGAGACCCUGGACCUCCCUGCUGCUGGUGGACGCGGCUUUACUGUGGCUGCUUCAGGGCCCUCUGGGGACUUUGCUUCCUCAAGGGCUGCCAGGACUAUGGCUGGAGGGGACCCUGCGGCUGGGAGGGCUGUGGGGGCUGCUAAAGCUAAGAGGGCUGCUGGGAUUUGUGGGGACACUGCUGCUCCCGCUCUGUCUGGCCACCCCCCUGACUGUCUCCCUGAGAGCCCUGGUCGCGGGGGCCUCACGUGCUCCCCCAGCCAGAGUCGCUUCAGCCCCUUGGAGCUGGCUGCUGGUGGGGUACGGGGCUGCGGGGCUCAGCUGGUCACUGUGGGCUGUUCUGAGCCCUCCUGGAGCCCAGGAGAAGGAGCAGGACCAGGUGAACAACAAAGUCUUGAUGUGGAGGCUGCUGAAGCUCUCCAGGCCGGACCUGCCUCUCCUCGUUGCCGCCUUCUUCUUCCUUGUCCUUGCUGUUUUGGGUGAGACAUUAAUCCCUCACUAUUCUGGUCGUGUGAUUGACAUCCUGGGAGGUGAUUUUGACCCCCAUGCCUUUGCCAGUGCCAUCUUCUUCAUGUGCCUCUUCUCCUUUGGCAGCUCACUGUCUGCAGGCUGCCGAGGAGGCUGCUUCACCUACACCAUGUCUCGAAUCAACUUGCGGAUCCGGGAGCAGCUUUUCUCCUCCCUGCUGCGCCAGGACCUCGGUUUCUUCCAGGAGACUAAGACAGGGGAGCUGAACUCACGGCUGAGCUCGGAUACCACCCUGAUGAGUAACUGGCUUCCUUUAAAUGCCAAUGUGCUCUUGCGAAGCCUGGUGAAAGUGGUGGGGCUGUAUGGCUUCAUGCUCAGCAUAUCGCCUCGACUCACCCUCCUUUCUCUGCUGCACAUGCCCUUCACAAUAGCAGCGGAGAAGGUGUACAACACCCGCCAUCAGGAAGUGCUUCGGGAGAUCCAGGAUGCAGUGGCCAGGGCGGGGCAGGUGGUGCGGGAAGCCGUUGGAGGGCUGCAGACCGUUCGCAGUUUUGGGGCCGAGGAGCAUGAAGUCUGUCGCUAUAAAGAGGCCCUUGAACAAUGUCGGCAGCUGUAUUGGCGGAGAGACCUGGAACGCGCCUUGUACCUGCUCGUAAGGAGGGUGCUGCACUUGGGGGUGCAGAUGCUGAUGCUGAGCUGUGGGCUGCAGCAGAUGCAGGAUGGGGAGCUCACCCAGGGCAGCCUGCUUUCCUUUAUGAUCUACCAGGAGAGCGUGGGGAGCUAUGUGCAGACCCUGGUAUACAUAUAUGGGGAUAUGCUCAGCAACGUGGGAGCUGCAGAGAAGGUUUUCUCCUACAUGGACCGACAGCCAAAUCUGCCUUCACCUGGCACGCUUGCCCCCACCACUCUGCAGGGGGUUGUGAAAUUCCAAGACGUCUCCUUUGCAUAUCCCAAUCGCCCUGACAGGCCUGUGCUCAAGGGGCUGACGUUUACCCUACGUCCUGGUGAGGUGACGGCGCUGGUGGGACCCAAUGGGUCUGGGAAGAGCACAGUGGCUGCCCUGCUGCAGAAUCUGUACCAGCCCACAGGGGGACAGGUGCUGCUGGAUGAAAAGCCCAUCUCACAGUAUGAACACUGCUACCUGCACAGCCAGGUGGUUUCAGUUGGGCAGGAGCCUGUGCUGUUCUCCGGUUCUGUGAGGAACAACAUUGCUUAUGGGCUGCAGAGCUGCGAAGAUGAUAAGGUGAUGGCGGCUGCCCAGGCUGCCCACGCAGAUGACUUCAUCCAGGAAAUGGAGCAUGGAAUAUACACAGAUGUAGGGGAGAAGGGGAGCCAGCUGGCUGCGGGACAGAAACAACGUCUGGCCAUUGCCCGGGCCCUUGUACGAGACCCGCGGGUCCUCAUCCUGGAUGAGGCUACUAGUGCCCUAGAUGUGCAGUGCGAGCAGGCCCUGCAGGACUGGAAUUCCCGUGGGGAUCGCACAGUGCUGGUGAUUGCUCACAGGCUGCAGGCAGUUCAGCGCGCCCACCAGAUCCUGGUGCUCCAGGAGGGCAAGCUGCAGAAGCUUGCCCAGCUCCAGGAGGGACAGGACCUCUAUUCCCGCCUGGUUCAGCAGCGGCUGAUGGACUGAGGCCCCAGGGAUACUGGGCCCUCUUCUCAGGGGCGUCUCCAGGACCCAGAGCUGUUCCUGCUUUGAGUUUCCCUAGAGCUGUGCGGCCAGAUAGCUGUUCCUGAGUUGCAAGCACGAUGGAGAUUUGGACACUGUGUGCUUUUGGUGGGGUGGAGAGGUGGGGUGGGGUGGGGUGUGGUGGGGUGGAGGCUGUCUGUGUCCAGGAAACUUAAUUCCCUGGUGACUAGAGCUUUGCCUGGUGAUGAGGAGUAUUUUGUGGCAUAAUACAUAUAUUUUAAAAUAUUUUCCUUCUUACGUGAACUGUAUACAUUCAUAUAGAAAAUUUAGACAAUAUAAAAAAGUACAAAGAAGAAAAGUAAAAGUACCCAUUGUUUCACUUCCUGGAGAUAACCAUAGUUGCUAUUUUGCUGCCUGUUCCAUCAGUCGUUUAUCUGUUGUUUGAGAUAGAAAUUAACCAAAAAUGACAUAAAUAUUCAUGAGAUUGCCUUCCUAUAUCCCUCCUUGUUCCUACCAGUGUCUGCUAUUUUGAAGAAGCUAGGGUCUGGAGGGACAGAGAACAGUUCCCUGAUUAACAGUAUUAAUAAUGACAUUGGUAACAGCUACCAUUUAUAGAGUUUUAAUGUGAGUAGGAGCUAUGCUAAGUGUUUUUCAUGUAUUAUCGUUUUUAAUCAUUAUCUCCAACCCUAUGAGGUUGGUUAUUAUCCCCAUUUUACAGAUGAGGAAACUGAAGCUCAAAGAGGCUCAAUGACUUUCCCAAGGUGGUCGUAGUGGUGGAGUUGGAGUUUGAACACAGGCCUGACCCUAGAGUCCACACCCUGACCCAAUCAAUUAUAUUGCAUCUUGGGUCCAUAAACCCUAAUCCAUAAUCCCAUCAAGAAAAGCUCUGCUGCUCUUAGCUCUAAAUAAUUCAGAAUCUAUUCUCUUCUCUCCAGUCCCGUUGUUAUAGUCUUCACUCAUAGACAGCCCAUCUGUCUCACCCUCUCCUGUUGUAUCCAGCUCCACGACAAACUUCUGCCUUCCCCAACACCUUUGUGCCUUUGCAUAUGGUGUUUUCUUGCCCAUUUUCUGCUCGACUCGCCCCUGAUUUUCAAGUUCAAGACUUAACUCAGGGUUCAGGUCUUCCAGGAGGCCUUACUUAUGUCGUCAGUCUGGGGAACUCUCCAUGUGCUUCUAUCACUGUGCGGUUACCUCUUUCACAGCCCUUUUAAAGUUCUAUCUUCCCUUUCCCACCUUUUUUGACCUUCCACUAGACCAUGAGCACCUGGGCGGAAAGCCAUAUAUCUUAUUAAGCUUUAUAUCUGCUACCUGGCCGAGGGCCUAAUUCAUAGUGGAGAAUAAAUAGUCAAUUGAAUAAAUGAAUAAAUAUCUCCACCAUCGUACUAAUCUUAAUCCUCCCUGCCCACUCCCACCACUGAAAAUGCAACAUUGUACACAUCACUGGUUGUUGGGAGGGACUUACCUUGGAAAGUUGCUAUUCUAGGAAAGAGAAACCUUCAUAUUCCUGGAAACAGCAGGUAGUUUCCAGUGCUGGCAAUGAAUUCCCCAGAACUGCUGUUUUGGAUUUUUUCUUGCCUGGCAGCUGUUGGGAGCAGGGUGCAGUGAGGAUGGGGUGAGAGUGGGCAGUUUCUUGUGCAGAUUUGCCUUUCUUUCAUCCUGGGGCUGACUUGCAGCUCCACACCCAUCCAUCUCUCAAAUUUCACAGAGGGUAAAAUAGGCAUUUGGAGAGAAAGAACUCUGGCCUGAUUCCUUUCUCUCCCACAAAUGUCCUUUAUUCAUAAAACAGGAAUAGUAAUUCCUGUAUCUCCCAACUACAUGGAAGCUGCAGCCCUCACAGAAGAAGAUGAUCUGAGAAAUUCUUUGAUUUCCUCAGUACAGUUAUACCCAUGCAUCAUAAUACUUUAAGCCUGGAAGGCAUCUUAAAAAUAAUGCAACAGUCAAACCUAAUUUUACAGAGAAACUGACAUGAAAUCACGCAGCUAAUCAUGAUAAAGCUGGGUGGAAAACUUAUCUUGAUGGGCAGUACAGGAAGAUGCAGUAGACCUUAAGAUGUCCUGAAAGUUUCUUAUCUCAGGGGAAACUCCCAGGUAGGCUUUAUGUCAGGGACACAGAAAAAUGCUCCCUGAAAGUCAAAAUAUUCGGGCUAGACAGACAAAUUCCUGUAAGUGUGGUUUGUCUGGGAACCACAGAUGUCACUAAUCCUGGUUUGCUCCAGAGUUCUUUUUGUUCACUCCUACCCCCCAUCACCAUUUGAUUGAUCUCCUUACCCUGUAAUUUCCCCUUCUUGUCGCUUACCUGCAGUAUCUUUCCCACCCAGGCAUGCCUUAUUCUUUCUAAAGGAAAGUAUGAAUGGAGAGGGGAAAGCUUGGGAAACUGAUAGAUUUCCUUGGAUGCCAAAACACCUCCAUAGCCUGUCUGCCCGGCCCUAUGUGGAAACAGCAUUGAGUUUCAAGUCCUUUAUGCCUCCACCCAGGGAUAGCCACUUGGAAUCCACAUGGCAAUUGUGAAACAAGCAGGAAAUGCGUAAUUGUCAGAAUUUUGUGGGGAAAGGACUAGGGAAUAAGGAAAACAAAGAUCUUCCUUGUGUUUUAGAGCUGUCAGCUAGAGGAGCACCUGCUUGAGUCUGAUGCCAUCUAAUGGUCCCAGAAGAAACUGGGUUUUGAACCUAGAGUUCCAUGGACUCUUAGGAAUUAGACUACUACUACUACUAAGCAUUCACUGGUGCUUACUAUGUGCUAUUGCUGUGCCAAGUAUCUGAAACCUGUCUUCUUACCUUAUUUUUCAAGAUAAUUCUAUGUGGCAGGUAUUACUAUCUCAAUUCUAAGAGUGAGAAAAUGGAGUUUUAGAAACAUUUACUAACUUGCCUGGGUCACAUAGCUAAGGAAGAGGUGGACUUGCCCAGCUUUGCAUAAAACUCCUCAAAAGAGUUGCCUAUACUCCCUGAUUCCACUUAUCUUCCUACUAUCCUCUUUUUAAAAUAUAUUAUUUAUUUAUUUAAAUAAGCAAUAUAUGAAUGUGGUUUGAAAUUCAAAAGACACAAAGAAGUAUACAGAGGAAAGCCUCACUCUCAAUCCUUCUCAAGGUUUGCUAAUUCCUCUUGCAUAGGCAAUCCGUUCUUCCAGCUUUGUGUUUAUCUUUCCAGAGAAGUUUACUGUGUAUUAAGCAAAUAUGUAUAUCUUUAUUCUUGCUCAGUAUUUUCGCAAACAGCAGCUGUCUAAGUUCACUGUUCUGAACUUUAUUUUUUAAAUUAAAAAUAUAUGGCUAUGUAGUAUUCUAUUUUA